GCAGCCCCGGGCGCCGCGCGUCCUGCCCGGCCUGCGGCCCCAGCCCUUGCGCCGCUCGUCCGACCCGCGAUCGUCCACCAGACCGUGCCUCCCGGCCGCCCGGCCGGCCCGCGUGCAUGCUUCGGUCUGGGCCAGCCUCUGGGCCGUCCGUCCCCACUGGCCGGGCCAUGCCGAGUCGCCGCGUCGCCAGACCGCCGGCUGCGCCGGAGCUGGGGGCCUUAGGGUCCCCCGACCUCUCCUCACUCUCGCUCGCCGUUUCCAGGAGCACAGGUUCAUCCAGCACAGAUGCCUAAGAAGGAUUUUCCCAGUUCAAGUGACUUGAGAUGAAUUGGAGAUCAUCGACGAGUACAUCAAGGAGAACGGCUUCGGCCUGGACGGGGGACAGCCGGGCCCGGGCGAGGGGCUGCCACGCCUGGUGUCUCGCGGGGCUGCGUCCCUGAGCACGGUCACCCUGGGCCCUGUGGCGCCCCCAGCCACGCCGCCGCCUUGGGGCUGCCCCCUGGGCCGACUAGUGUCCCCAGCGCCGGGCCCGGGCCCGCAGCCGCACCUGGUCAUCACGGAGCAGCCCAAGCAGCGCGGCAUGCGCUUCCGCUACGAGUGCGAGGGCCGCUCGGCCGGCAGCAUCCUUGGGGAGAGCAGCACCGAGGCCAGCAAGACGCUGCCCGCCAUCGAGCUCCGGGAUUGUGGAGGGCUGCGGGAGGUGGAGGUGACUGCCUGCCUGGUGUGGAAGGACUGGCCUCACCGAGUCCACCCCCACAGCCUCGUGGGGAAAGACUGCACCGACGGCAUCUGCAGGGUGCGGCUCCGGCCUCACGUCAGCCCCCGGCACAGUUUUAACAACCUGGGCAUCCAGUGUGUGAGGAAGAAGGAGAUUGAGGCUGCCAUUGAGCGGAAGAUUCAACUGGGCAUUGACCCCUACAACGCUGGGUCCCUGAAGAACCAUCAGGAAGUAGACAUGAAUGUGGUGAGGAUCUGCUUCCAGGCCUCAUAUCGGGACCAGCAGGGACAGAUGCGCCGGAUGGAUCCUGUGCUUUCCGAGCCCGUCUAUGACAAGAAAUCCACAAACACAUCAGAGCUGCGGAUUUGCCGAAUUAACAAGGAAAGCGGGCCGUGCACCGGUGGCGAGGAGCUCUACUUGCUCUGCGACAAGGUGCAGAAAGAGGACAUAUCAGUGGUGUUCAGCAGGGCCUCCUGGGAAGGUCGGGCUGACUUCUCCCAGGCCGACGUGCACCGCCAGAUUGCCAUUGUGUUCAAGACGCCGCCCUACGAGGACCUGGAGAUUGUCGAGCCCGUGACAGUCAACGUCUUCCUGCAGCGGCUCACCGAUGGGGUCUGCAGCGAGCCAUUGCCUUUCACGUACCUGCCUCGCGACCAUGACAGCUACGGCGUGGACAAGAAGCGGAAACGGGGGAUGCCCGACGUCCUUGGGGAGCUGAACAGCUCUGACCCCCAUGGCAUCGAGAGCAAACGGCGGAAGAAAAAGCCGGCCAUCCUGGACCACUUCCUGCCCAACCACGGCUCAGGCCCGUUCCUCCCGCCGUCAGCCCUGCUGCCAGACCCUGACUUCUUCUCUGGCACCGUGUCCCUGCCCGGCCUGGAGCCCCCUGGCGGGCCUGACCUCCUGGACGAUGGCUUUGCCUACGACCCUACGGCCCCCACACUCUUCACCAUGCUGGACCUGCUGCCCCCGGCACCGCCACACGCUAGCGCUGUUGUGUGCAGCGGAGGUGCCGGGGCCGUGGUUGGGGAGACCCCCGGCCCUGAACCACUGACACUGGACUCGUACCAGGCCCCGGGCCCCGGGGAUGGAGGCACCGCCAGCCUUGUGGGCAGCAACAUGUUCCCCAAUCAUUACCGCGAGGCGGCCUUUGGGGGCGGCCUCCUAUCCCCGGGGCCUGAAGCCACGUAGCCCCGCGAUGCCAGAGGAGGGGCACUGGGUGGGGAGGGAGGUGGAGGAGCCGUGCAAUCCCAACCAGGAUGUCUAGCACCCCCAUCCCCUUGGCCCUUCCUCAUGCUUCUGAAGUGGACAUAUUCAGCCUUGGCGAGAAGCUCCGUUGCACGGGUUUCCCCUUGAGCCCAUUUUACAGAUGAGGAAACUGAGUCCGGAGAGGAAAAGGGACAUGGCUCCCGUGCACUAGCUUGUUACAGCUGCCUCUGUCCCCACAUGUGGGGGCACCUUCUCCAGUAGGAUUCGGAAAAGAUUGUACAUAUGGGAGGAGGGGGCAGAUUCCUGGCCCUCCCUCCCCAGACUUGAAGGUGGGGGGUAGGUUGGUUGUUCAGAGUCUUCCCAAUAAAGAUGAGUUUUUGAGCC